GGUCCUCGCCUCGCUUCACGGUCUUUACCGCUCAGCUUCCCGGAGUCCGCGCAGGAGCGCGUCUGAAUAGGAAGCGUUUUCGGACGUGGAUGCGGCGUUUUGUCGCUGCCAGUGGUGUCUGGAGAGGUUCGGGCUCGGUCCUCAGGUCCUGGCUCCCAGAAGCAAAAUAACUCAAGUGAAGCAAUGAAGGAAGAAGAAGGAGGUUGCUGGCCUUGGAUAUCAUAAUUUCUGGGGACAACUUUAAGUGGACACUAAUAUUUCUGACUAGGAAAACUUCAAAAACUUCAUGGCAAAUGCAGAAGAGACAAAGACGUAUAGUCCAUGUUAUCCACUAUUUUCUGAGCACAGAAGAAAAUGAUCAAGACCCAGGAAUCACUGACCCUGGAGGAUGUGGCUGUGGAAUUCAGCUGGGAGGAGUGGCAGCUCCUGGACACUGCUCAGAAGAACCUGUACCGGGAUGUGAUGGUGGAGAACUAUAACCACCUAGUAUCACUGGGGUAUCAAACUAGCAAACCAGAUGUACUCUCCAAGUUGGCACAUGGACAAGAACCAUGGACAACAGAUGCUAAAAUUCAGAAUAAAAAUUGUCCAGGAAUCGGGAAAGUUGACAGUCAUCUGCAAGAGCACUCUCCAAACCAAAGACUUCUGAAGAGCGUGCAGCAAUGCAAUGGACAGAAUACACUUAGAAAUAUUGUACAUCUCAGCAAGACACAUUUUCCUAUAGUGCAAAAUCAUGAUACAUUUGACUUGUACAGAAAAAAUUUGAAAUCAAGUUUAAGUUUAAUCAACCAGAAGAGAAGACAUGGAAUAAAUAACCCUGUUGAGUUUAUUGGAGGUGAGAAAACACUUCUACAUGGUAAGCAUGAACGUACGCAUACUAAAACUAGAUUUUCUGAAAAUGCAAAAUGUAUCCAUACUAAAUUCCAAGUCUUCAAGCAUCAGAGGACUCAGAAAAUUGAGAAACCCCAUGCAUGCAUUGAAUGUGAGCAAACCUUCCUUAGGAAGUCUCAGCUCAUUUACCAUGAGAACAUUUGUAUACAAGAGAAUCCUGGAAGUGGUCAAUGUGAGAAAUUAUCCAGAAGUGUCCUGUUCACUAAGCAUCUGAAAACUAAUACAACAGACAAAAUCUGUAUACCCAAUGAAUAUAGAAAAGGCUCUACUGUGAAGAGUAGUCUCAUUACACAUCAACAAACCCAUACAGAAGAGAAAUCCUAUAUGUGCAGUGAGUGUGGAAAGGGCUUUACAAUGAAGCGCUAUCUAAUUGCUCAUCAGCGAACUCAUAGUGGAGAGAAACCUUAUGUGUGCAAAGAAUGUGGAAAAGGUUUCACUGUGAAGAGCAAUCUCAUUGUACAUCAGCGAACUCAUACAGGGGAGAAACCCUAUAUAUGCAGUGAAUGUGGAAAAGGCUUCACCAUGAAGCGCUAUCUUGUUGUACAUCAGCGAACUCAUACUGGAGAGAAACCCUAUAUGUGCAGUGAAUGUGGAAAAGGCUUUACCGUGAAGAGCAAUCUCAUUGUACAUCAGCGCUCCCACACAGGAGAAAAAUCUUACAUAUGCAGCGAAUGUGGAAAAGGCUUCACUGUCAAACGCACUCUCGUUAUACAUCAGCGAACUCAUACAGGAGAGAAAUCUUACAUAUGCAAUGAAUGUGGUAAAGGCUUCACCACAAAGCGCACUCUUAUUAUACAUCAGCGAACUCAUACAGGAGAAAAACCCUAUGAAUGCAAUGAAUGUGGUAAAGCCUUCAGCCAGAAAAUAUGCCUCAUACAACAUGAGAGAUGUCAUACAGGAAAGACUCCCUUUGUAUGUACCGAGUGCGGAAAAUCCUAUUCACACAAAUAUGGCCUCAUUACCCAUCAGAGAAUUCACACAGGAGAGAAACCUUAUGAGUGCAAUGAAUGUGGAAAAGCCUUCACCACAAAGUCAGUACUCAAUGUACAUCAAAGAACGCAUACAGGAGAGAGGCCGUAUGGAUGCAGUGAUUGUGAGAAAGCCUUCUCCCACUUAUCAAACCUUGUCAAACAUAAGAAAAUGCACACAAGAGAAAUGGGUAGAAUCAGUCAAGUUGAAAACUCCUGUAAUGGAGAGUCACAGCUCCUUCCUUAUAAGUGAACUCAUGCAGAAGAAAACCCUACUAGUGCCGUGACUAUGGAAAUGCCUUUUGUGGCAACUCAGACUUCAUUAAACAUCAGUGUGUUUCUAGCCAAUUGGAACAUAAACAUGGUGCUGCCUGUUGACAGAUGUGUGUCUGUCCUCAGGAGGUGAAAUAAUUUGCCCUAGAGAUCAAUUUGAUGAAUACAGUAAAUAAGGUAGUGCCUUUAGUGGUCUUUUACCUCAUAUUUUCUGUCAAUGAAAAUACGUUGAAUAAACUAUAUUAAUGUGGAGAUGUUUUGAGCAAUAAUUUCUGCUCAUAUGUCUGAAAAGUAUACAGAGAUAAAUUCUGUGAAUACAAAGACUAAGAAAAGUCUUCUGUGGAAAGAUAGACUUUAUUAUCAGGUUUCAUCAUAGAUUUCAACGUAAGUGAGCUUAUUGUUGAUAGAAACAUGAUGACCAUGACAAAGUCUUUACUCAGAAAUAUGACCUCAGUGAGUGUCAAAGUUUACACUGGAAAAUAACUUUAAGGUGACAGUAUUGAUGGCAGGAUUUCAGCGACGCACUCUGCUUCAUCAUUUGUCAGGAGAUCACAUAGAAAGUAAAAUUGUUCCGAACAUGCUAUCAAAUAAAUGUGGAACACCUUUAGCAAACUAUCAACAGCUCAUGAAGGCAUGAAAUGUGGUGAAAAUGAUGAAUAUUUGAGUGCUUUUUCUUAAUAAGUAUAACCUUAAACAUCAGCUAAUACACCUGGUGUGCAUUUUCAGUCAGGAUACCUUAAUCCUCAUUUCUAGUUGCCUUGCCAAUGAUUCCAUAAUAUACUGUCUCAUUACUGUUUAUUUUUACUGUUGUGUAAAAUUGUGGUAUAAUGAGAAAUACAUUUGGUCUUUGUUCCUGGUUCCUGGCAUAGAGCUCCUAAAACGCUUAGAAUUUCAUGAGUGAUAAGAGUUUUUUGGUUUUGUUUUGUUUUUGCUGUUGUUGUUAUUCAUAGCACUGCCCUUUUAAUUACACCUGAUUAUACUACUGAAGUGACUUAUGGUUGCUCCCCUAGACAGCCUCAGAAUGGGGCUGUUCUCUAGGAAGAUCAAGUAACUAGAGGAUGGAGACUUUGUGCCCCAUUUCUCCCACCUCCUGGAAGGGGAGGGGUGCUGGAGAUUAGAUUAGACAAUGAGAUUAAGAGAACUCCAAAUAGCCCAAGAGGGUGGUGCACCCCCAACUUCAUAGGGGUAGAGGCUCCUGAGAUUAGGAGAACCCUUUUUAGGCUUUACUCUAUGUACCUCUUCAUUUGAGUGUUCAUUUGCGUCCUUUAUAACCAGUAAAACAAAGUACGCUGUUUUCUUGAGUUUUGUGAGCCCUGUAGCAAAUUAUCAAACCUGAGUAGGGCAGUGGGAACUCGGAAUUUAUCACCAUUCAGAACUGCAGGUUGUCCUUGUGAGUGGCAUCUGAUGUGGGGGAAGUCUUGGACUGAGCCCCUUAACUUGUGGAGUCUGCACUAAUUUAGACUGCACUAACUAACUUGCACUGCACUAACUUGGACUGCACUAACUUGUGGAGUCUGCACUAACUUGGAGAAGUUAGUGUCAGAAUUGAAUUAUAGAACACCCAGUUGUUCAGAAUUGAAUUGUAGAACACCCAAUUGGUGUGGGAGAAUUAGAGAAUUUAUUUGUGUCAGAAAAUACUCCAGAACAACCACCCCAUAUUAUGAUUAGCUCUUUUCCUUUCUUUGGCUCUGAGCUUAAUUGUACAUUAAGCAAACUUAAGUAGAAAAGAAACUGAAUAUGUUAAAUAUAUUAACAACAUAUUUGGACUUGCUUAACUAAGAUUAUAGAGAUGAUCAGUUUAUAAAACCACCUUCAACUUAAAUAAAUUUGAACUCGAAAUUGCAAAAGCAGUCUAGAGGCUUUGCUAGUAUCCUUCAACCAAUUUCUAGUAAAAAUAUCCUAUAUAACCAUAAUUAUCAAAACCAGAAAAACAACAUUGGUAGGAUACUAUAAAGUACUAAUCUUAUUUUGGAUUUGACGAAUUUUUACAUGUUUUUUUCUUUUUUAGUUUGUACUCUAAGAAGUUGUAUUACAUGUACAGAUUCGUGUAACCACUGCAACCACAUAAAACUAAUGAACACAAAGUCCCUCAUGCUACCUUUUUAUGCUUACACUCCAUCCAAACCUAACUCUGCCAACCACUUUUCUCCUAUCAGUAUAAUUUCAUCAUUUCAUGAAUAUGAUAAAAAUAAAAUUGUUUUUGUAAAUGGUUUUUAUAAAUUUUAUAUAAAUAAGUUAUAUGAAUUUUUAUUGAUAGAGAGUAUGUAAGCUUUUGGCAUUUUUGUCACUCAGCAAAUUACUCCUAAGGUUUAUAUGAGUUGAUGAAUAGUUGUUUUAUUAUUUUUUUUUACCACCAUGUAUCUAACCAGAUGAAAGUUGUUUAUAUUUGAGAGUAGUAUACAUAUUUGAUGUAGUAGUUUAUCCAUUCACCUAUGAGAUAUAUUUGCACUGUUUUCCUGGUUUUAAGUGCUAUAAAUAAAGAUGCUGUGAAAUCUA